GAUGCGGGCGCUCUCGGCGCACAGCGCGCGGCGCUCCUGCUCCCCGGCGGACGCCCGGCCGCCCUGCAGAUAAAUGCGUCGCCUUCCUCGAGAGUGAGCGAGGGCGGGCGAGGGAGACGCAGACGCCGCCUGUGACAGUGGCAAUUCCCUGCGCCCCACAUCACAUUUGUCUGCCACAGCAGCAACAACAGAAAAGCGGAGGGAGGGAGGGAGGCGGGAGGAGGGGAGCAGAGCUCCGCAAGUCUUGGGCUCUGCGUGGAGGUUGCGUUUGGCUGGCGUCCCCGACCCCGGGCUUUUUGCACGGCAGCUCUCUCUGCGCAGCGCCGGGCGGCCGUAGUCGCUCCGCGGCGCGACUCCGCGGUCUCGUGGCGAGCGCGCGUGGGCGAGUGGCCGCGGACACUCUGGCCUCGCGAGGGAAGCCGCGCCGCGUCCUCGCCCCGUCGCCCCGCGGGCCGGCCGAGACGACGGGAAGUUUUAUUUGCAGCUCGGAGCCUGUGGCGGAUGGUGGGACUCUCCGGCCCUGUGCAGUUAUCAAAUGAUAAGAACUGAGCACACUGGAUGAAAUAAUACUUGCACUGGGAGCACUAAGGUAGGCGCUUUACAAGUAUUAUCUCCUCAUAUCAUCCUGAUAAGUUAGGUGUUAUUAUCUUACUUUGGAGAUUUAAAUCUGAAGCUUAGAGAGGUUAAGUGACUUGUCCAAGGUCAAAUAGCUGAUGAGUAAGUGUAAGAACUGAGAUUCCAAUCCAGCCAGAGUGCGUAUACAGUGGGCUUCUAAAUGGCCCGCGUGUGUAGGCCACAGUCAUUUAUAACACUUUAUUUUUUGAAAAUUAAAUUAUAUCUGCAACAGAGAAGAUAUUUAAGAGCUUCCUACCAUUUAAAAUUGCCUGGUUUGUUAACUCACUGGUCAUAUUGCGUUGUUGAUACUUAGUUGGUUGCCUACCUUCUGAUUAAUUUGUUACUUAAAAAUAUUUGUAGGAUUUUGAAAUAAUGCCUUAUCACAAGAGAAAGGGGCUUGAAGAAAGACCAGAUCAUAUUCCAUUAUCAGUUAUUCCCUGUUUACUCAGUCAGUAUUUAGUGAACACCUUUUGUGUGCCAGGCACUGUGCUAGGCACUGGGUAUGGGCAUUGUUGAAUAAACAUGGCCAUGCUCUUGCAGCCCUGCCAAUGGAAUGAAUAGAGUGCAUCAAUGUAGGGUCCAAAGGUGUAAGAAAUUAAGAUUGGAUCUCAUUUCUACAACAGCUGACAUGCUCAAUUGUGAGAUAAUCCAAUGCAUAAAAAGCUGCUAGAGUGCACUUAUGCCUUAAAGGUUGUAUGGACUCUGCUGCAGUUCCCAGUCACAGUGUCCUGCUGCUCAGUGUGGGACAAAGGGCUGGCUUCAUAGCCGUGGAUGUCGUGGGUGAUUUCCAUGCUGCCCUAUCUCUAUACAGCACCAGUGGGAAUGGGCUUCUGUGAACAGUACCUGGCAGGUAAAAGGUUGCAGAGCCUGAUGUAGACCCAAAGUACUAUAGUAUAAAGAAGAGAAAAAGAUCACAGGUCACAGAAGUAGCCACGGAAAGGUUUGCCAAAGUCAUGGGGAUUGAAUUGGGCUUUUGUGGCAUUUCAUUGAGUGGGAUUCAUUUGUUUUUCUUUUCAUUUGGGGCUACAACUAGGUUCCUAGUCCAGUUCCAAAUGUGGAGGGUAGAGUAAUGAGCACCCCCCAGAUGAGACCCUAGCUCUCACAGAGCUUGCAGUUUGGGUGGGGGAGGGAGAAAGAUAAAAAAGAAGUUACUAAGAUUAUUUCAUGUAGUGCUAAAUAUAAUUAAGACAAUUAAGAAACAAUGUUAGAAUGAUGCAGAGGGUGGGGGGACAUGGUAGUGAGACUUUAUUUCAAAUGGUUGGGGAAAUCAUCUGUCAGGUGGUGACUCUUGAACUAAAGCCUGAGGGUUGAGGAAGAACUGGCCGUGCAGCAGUCUAUGGGAAGGGCCGUGAAGUCAGUGAACGAAGCCACCAGCAUGAGAGGAAGUGUUCCAUCAGGGAGUUUAUCCAGCCAGAGAAGAGCUGCACUCUGGAAGGGCGUGGUUGGAGUGGAGGCUGAAAACUGUAGAUGAGUGCCAAGUGAUGGAGGGUCUUGUAUGUGAGAUUAGGCAAGAAUAAGGACUGUGUGUUUCUGUGUGUGAAUGUAGGAGAUGAGUAGUUAGAAGAGAGAAGGAGAAUCUGGAUGAGUGUAUGCAUGGAAGCUUAAGGAAGCUUGUGAAACUAGGAUAAUGACAUUUAGUUCACAUGACCUGCGAUGAGGGGCACCCAAAUCACACAGUGUCUCAGUUACUUCCUGUUGGAAGUUGAGUAUAGUCCUGAAGUGAGGCAUAGAUGGUGCUCUGUUCACUACUCCUUCAAAUUAGAGGGACACACAAUUGCUUACAAAGAAAUGGUGAAGCUUUGACAAAGGUAAGCUACAGUCCAGUGCCAGAAACUGUACUUACCAAGGUAAUAUUUCCUAAGUCAGAUAUGCUAUAACAGGUUCCUUUUAUGGUGAUUCCCCUUGGAAACAAAAACUAAGUGUACAUUUGUUCAUGUAAAAUAAUAGCUUUUAUGAUAUAAAAUGUUUCUAUGAAGGAAAAGAAAAGAGUUAGAGUUAAGGUUUGAUUCAACCCAGGUUGAUAGAUAAAAAGAGGUGUGUUUAAAUGCUCAUUUUUGGAAUAACCAUGUAUCAUUUACUAAAGGAAAAAGUGCCCCAAAUGUUGAUAGAAUUCUCUAGAGAAAUGUGUUUAGGCAGUGAAAGGAUUCCUGGCAGUGAUUGAGAAAUACAGUAAUGGGGAACUGCACUUGAUCUCUUUUGAGGUUGAUUCUGAUGUGUGUAGUCUUUACAUCCUAUUAAAUUUUUGAAAGAUAAACUGAUACAAGAAUGAUUUGCCAAGGCCAUAUGAGGUUAACUGAAUUCAAAUAGAAGGUUCUCUCAAGUUAUUGCAUUCCUUAGAAAAUAAAUACAUUGCGCAUAUGGUUAAGAUUGAUCAAAAAAGUAUUCUGUAUGCCAAUGAUUACAUUCCCAUCUGUGAUUAAGGUUUUCUGUCUGCAUCUGGUUUUCACAUUAUAUUUCUGUAACAAGAAUCCUUUAUAUAGCAGAGUUCACUUUCUGUAUUUUCUAUUAGUUGCAGCUUGAACUACUGCACGGAUCGCAGAUUUGCACAUGUGGUUUUCAUUACUUCAUACCAUUGAGAAAAAGUAAUAUUUGUUUGGGAAUGUAUGUUUUCCACAAUUUCCAUGGUAAUACAACAUGUUGAGCCUUUUAAAUAACACUUGUAGAACUACAAAUUGUUUGAGGCAUUCUGCUCUUGGUGGAGCUUAGCUUUUAAACUUUUCUCAGUAUGUUCCCCUCGUAAUGAGGUUUUACAAAUUUGAGGGCUGAGCAUCCAGAUCUGAACAAAGCAAUUAUUAAAGAUAGAGAGAUUUUAUUAUCACUUCCAUGUGACAGACUUCAGUGCGGAAUAGGUCUCAGAAAUACCUGAACAUCGUGCUUAUUACCAUUACUUAUUUUAUUAUUAUUUCAUAUUGGAAGGGCAUUUAAUGUGUUGGAGAUAUGAAGCACAAAUGUGACACUCCAGUCAUUGUUUUGAAAAAUCCAAAGAUUAGCUCUUUUUUUUUUUUUAGUUACCCUUUUGAUUGUGAUAUAUUGUUUCAUAUAUAAAAUAGUUAAGUGGUGAAAAUCCUCAUGGGUGACUUUAGAUUUACAUUGUAUAUUGUUUGAAACUGUAUUUGUACACUAUGUUAACAUUUAAGAAUUUAUAAAUAUGCACAUUUAAAAUACUUUGUUAUCACCAUGUUCCUGCCAAUUUUCUUCAUUCACUUCAAAAAACUCUGAUUAAAAUAGAUACAAGUGAAGUUAAAAAGUAAAGCAGUAUAUUCCAAAUUGAGAGAUCAUUUUUAAUUGAGAAAUUUGUCUUAAAGUUUAUCACAUGGUAAUUUUAUGUGCCUCAAAACCAAGAUUAAGUACCCCAUUUUUGUUAAACCCAGACAUUGGUCUGAUAUUUAGCAGUCAUGAGAAGGAAGAUAUAGACUUAGACUCUAGAGGAUUUGUAUAUGCUUUGCCUGGUUCGUUUGCUCAGUAGAGAUUAUUAACUAUGGCUCAUAUAGGGGCAUGAUCCACUUUUGUCAGGCUCUCUGAUGGCCUUUGUUGAUGGUUGCUGAAGCACAAAAUAUAUAUUAUGAUUGAAUCUAAGAAGAGUAUACAUUUUCUUUUUUCCCAAUAUUUGUUUAGCCUAUAUAAAAUGUUUUUUACCUUUGUACAGAAACAUUGGAAAUAACAGAAUUGUGCAGAAAAGUUACUCACAUUGCCAUCUUCCAGAAAUAAUCAUAUUUAACAUCUAGAUGUAUUUACUUUCAGUCUUCCCCGCUGUGUGCACCCUCCCCCACUCCACUAUUUGAGUACUUACACAACCUAUACGUGUACAUAUAUUUAUGUAUCUUGGUUAUAGCAUUGAAAUUUUUUGCUUUAUCAUUUGUUAAUAAAAUUGUUAGUAUUUAUAGUAAGCUAAAUGUUUCCAAGAUCCAGCUGAUUGUCUUUAAUGAUCUUUGCUUACUGCAAGGCAAUUCCCAACUAAGAAAUAUCUAGUAAUGUAUUUUAAUUAAUCAGUACUUAUUUAAUUUUUAAACCUUAAAGAGCAAGAAACAACUGAUUGCAUCACAAAAGAAUCAUAAUGUGGCACAUAAACUACAUUGAUUUUUUAAAAAAUAGAACCUGCUUGUUUUAUUUACAUCAGAAUAUGUUCACCGAUUUUAAUUUCUAGGAAGUAAUUUGGUCUCAAAAAAUAAUAGCUACAGCCUUAGUAAUUCCUUUUGAGACUGCUUUUAGAAAUCUUUCUUCCCUUGCAUUUGUUGAGUUCCUACCUUAUAUGUGUAUGAUUGUGCUGGACCCUUAUAUUUCCUAGUUUGUAAGAAUUACAUAGCAAUACUUUUUCUAUUCAUAGUAGUGAUAGUAGUGGUCUCAUUUUUAAUCAUAGUAGGUGAGGAAUAGACAAUAAAUAUUGUGAAUGAACAAAUUCUAAGUUUGUCAAAUAUAGCAGGAAAAAUGAGAAAAUUUAUAUUAUUAAAAGGAAGAAAAGGUGUAGAAGUUUGUUGAUUUGGUAAAAUAAUUCAACAAUAUUUGUUUCAUUAAUAUUUUUUAACUAUUCUAUUACAUAAGGAUUAUUCUUCACUGUUGUUUUAAACUAUGUGUGCUAAUAAUGGCAAUACUGAAAUUUCAGAACAGCGAAACAAAAUUUGAAUAAUGAAACAAACCACUUUGUUUUGAAACAGGAUUAACUUGUGUGUAAAAUUCCAUAAAUAAUAAUGUCUAAAUUGUUUUCUAAAGAAAACAUAAUAUCUGACAGAUUAUUUAUUUUUUUGAAACAGGUAAAAUGUAACAUUCUCUUAGGGUAUUGAUGUGCAUAUCUUUAAAACCAAUUUAAGAAAAGAAGAGCUUUCAGGGUGAGAAUGUAUCCAGCUUUGAGUCAGAUGAUUGGAAAAUUAAGAGUCCUUUAGAAAACAUCAUGAUAGGAACUGAGACAAUGGGGAUUGUUUUGGAUUCUUCUAAAAUUUAGAAGAGCUUGUAUCUGUUUUUUUUUUAAACAAAACAUAACAAAACUGGCCUAGUGUUAUCAUGUAAACAGAUGGGUAUGAUACUUCAGACUGGUUGUGAUAUAUGCAUUUUUUUUCCCUUUGUUGUUGUCAAUAGAAAAGAUUGAUCUCUGGGCUGGUGAACAUAAUCUCUGUCCCAGUCAGAAAAGGAGAGAGGAAAUUAGCAGAGCGAUUGGUGGAGAAUGAUAUCUGUCAAAAGAAACACUUGGAGAGCACUGAGUUUAGUAAUAGGUGACUGCCGGAAAAAAGGGAACUUUGAAUAUUGUCAAGAUCGUACUGAGAAGCACUCCACAAUGCCAGACUCACCUGUGGAUGUGAAGACGCAAUCUAGGCUGACUCCUCCAACAAUGCCACCUCCCCCAACUACUCAAGGAGCUCCAAGAACCAGUUCAUUUACACCGACAACGUUAACUAAUGGCACGAGCCAUUCUCCUACAGCCUUGAAUGGCGCCCCCUCACCACCCAAUGGCUUCAGCAAUGGGCCUUCCUCUUCUUCCUCCUCCUCUCUGGCUAAUCAACAGCUGCCCCCAGCCUGUGGUGCCAGGCAACUCAGCAAGCUGAAAAGGUUCCUUACUACCCUGCAGCAGUUUGGCAAUGACAUUUCACCCGAGAUAGGAGAAAGAGUUCGCACCCUCGUUCUGGGACUAGUGAACUCCACUUUGACAAUUGAAGAAUUUCAUUCCAAACUGCAAGAAGCUACUAACUUCCCACUGAGACCUUUUGUCAUCCCAUUUUUGAAGGCCAACUUGCCCCUGCUGCAGCGUGAGCUCCUCCACUGCGCAAGACUGGCCAAACAGAACCCUGCCCAGUACCUCGCCCAGCAUGAACAGCUGCUUCUGGAUGCCAGCACCACCUCACCUGUUGACUCCUCAGAGCUGCUUCUCGAUGUGAACGAAAACGGGAAGAGGCGAACUCCAGACAGAACCAAAGAAAAUGGCUUUGACAGAGAGCCUUUGCACUCAGAACAUCCAAGCAAGCGACCAUGCACUAUUAGCCCAGGCCAGCGGUACAGUCCAAAUAACGGCUUAUCCUACCAGCCCAAUGGCCUGCCUCACCCUACCCCACCUCCACCUCAGCAUUACCGUUUGGAUGAUAUGGCCAUUGCCCACCACUACAGGGACUCCUAUCGACACCCCAGCCACAGGGACCUCAGGGACAGAAACAGACCUAUGGGGUUGCAUGGCACACGUCAAGAAGAAAUGAUUGAUCACAGACUAACAGACAGAGAAUGGGCAGAAGAGUGGAAACAUCUUGACCAUCUGUUAAACUGCAUAAUGGACAUGGUAGAAAAAACAAGGCGAUCUCUCACCGUACUAAGGCGGUGUCAAGAAGCAGACCGGGAAGAAUUGAAUUACUGGAUCCGGCGGUACAGUGACGCCGAGGACUUAAAAAAAGGUGGCGGCAGUAGCAGCAGCCACUCUAGGCAGCAGAGUCCCGUCAACCCAGACCCAGUUGCACUAGACGCGCAUCGGGAAUUCCUUCACAGGCCUGCGUCUGGAUACGUGCCAGAGGAGAUCUGGAAGAAAGCUGAGGAGGCCGUCAAUGAGGUGAAGCGCCAGGCGAUGACGGAGCUGCAGAAGGCCGUGUCUGAGGCGGAGCGGAAAGCCCACGACAUGAUCACAACAGAGAGGGCCAAGAUGGAGCGCACGGUCGCCGAGGCCAAACGGCAGGCGGCGGAGGACGCACUGGCAGUUAUCAAUCAGCAGGAGGAUUCAAGCGAGAGUUGCUGGAAUUGUGGCCGUAAAGCGAGUGAAACCUGCAGUGGCUGUAACACAGCCCGAUACUGUGGCUCAUUUUGCCAGCACAAAGACUGGGAGAAGCACCAUCACAUCUGUGGACAGACCCUGCAGGCCCAGCAGCAGGGAGACACACCUGCAGUCAGCUCCUCUGUCACGCCCAACAGCGGGGCUGGGAGCCCGAUGGACACACCACCAGCAGCCACUCCGAGGUCAACCACCCCGGGAACCCCUUCCACCAUAGAGACAACCCCUCGCUAGACGUGAACUCAGAACUGUCGGAGGAAAGACAACACAACCAACGCGAAACCAAUUCCUCAUCCUCAGAUGCUCAAAGUUGUUUUUUUUGUUUGUUUGUUUAUUAGAUGAAUUAUCCUAUUUCAGUACUUCAGCAAGAGAGAACCUAACUGUAUCUUGAGGUGGUAGUAAAACACAGAGGGCCAGUAACGGGUCGUAAUGACUUAUUGUGGAUAACAAAGAUAUCUUUUCUUUAGAGAACUGAAAAGAGAGCAGAGAAUAUAACAUGAAAUGAUAGAUUUGACCUCCUCCCUGUUAUUUUCAAGUAGCUGGGAUUUUAAACUAGAUGACCUCAUUAACCGAUGCUUUACCAAACAGCAAACCAAGAGAUUGCUAAUUGCUGUUGAAAGCAAAAAUGCUAAUAUUAAAAGUCACAAUGUUCUUUAUAUACAAUAAUGGAAAAAAAAAAAAGAGGAAAACCCUCAAGGGCAUGAGCAUUGGAUACAGCAGUAGACAUUUUAACAAGAAGAUGAAUGGCGUCCGUGGGUUGCUAACUGAACUUUGAAGACCCGCUACAAAACGCGCAGAUGUGCAGCAGAUUGGAAGGAGACACAGAUGUUCGGUUUUUUUCCUGUUUCUGAAAAGAAAUAAUAAUAUCCAGGUCAACAGAAUGAAAAAUGAAAGAUGAUUUGCAAUGGGAUGUAUGAAUACAGCAGCAAGAAAAAAAAAUGCCAUAAUACAAAAGGCUCCAUAUAUAUAUAUAUAUAUAUAUAUAUACACACACACACACGCACAUAUACACACACACACACACACACACACACACACACACACACACACACACACACACACAAGUAAGAGACUCAGCCUGCAGUUAAUUAGCAUUCUGGCAGUUUUGACAUCAGCCAGCUGCCCUAAAUAACCCUUCAACGUUUCUUCACUUUUGCAAGGUUCCACAGAGUAAGACAUUGGGUCUAUUCCAGCUCAUUCAUUUUAUAUUGAAAAAAAUAAUUUUAAAAAUGGUGGCUUCAGCUCCAGCCCCUUUCCAAAAUUUUUCAACCCCACCCUGUUUGGAUUUUUAAUUAAAAACUAGUAGUUCUCUUGGUGUUAAAACACUUCUGUCCUGUGAGGUUUCCCAAUGGUGUUUUUCUUGUAAAUGUGUUGGACAAAUGUGAAGAUGCAUUGUAGUUUAACCAUAUGCCCACAUUUAGUCUCUUUAUUCCUAGUUGGUGAGAAACCUGUAUCUUUCUAUGCUGCUUUUAUAUCUGUAUGUAUUAGUGAUAUUUCUCUAGUAGUUAAAAAAAAAAAAAGGAAAAAAAGACUCUUUUUGGUUGUCCUCAAGAAAAGAAAAGAAGAAAAGCUAUCUUUCGGAGCUGCUAUUUCACUCUCUUAUAGGAUUUUUUUUUUUCCUGAAAACCAGCAUGCUUCACGGAAUGCUAACAUAUUGGUGUUUUUGUAAGAGGGAUGUACAUAAAUGUAUUUUGCACUGUCACAAUGACUCCCUAGGCAUGCUUUUUGUUUUUUUUUUUUUUUUUUUGAGCAAAUUCUUUUUAAAUAUGCUAGAGCCAUUUCAUCAAGUUUAGCUGUAGCAUAGAGUAGUCGUGGAAUUUUUCUUUUUUUUUUUUUUAAAUCAUUAUUAGGGACUUUUUUAAAAAAAUAAAAUAACAAGAUAUCCUACUUUAAAAAAAAAGGACAGUGCAUGCAUAUUGCUGUAAGGUCGUUUAAGUAUUUCUAAUUUUACAAAAGUAAAAAUCAUUAGAGCUCCAAAUGCUGAGGUGUAGAUUGACAGCUUUAACACUGCUGAAUGCCAGGUUAUACAGUAUUCUUACAAAAAGGGAAGUCAGCCAAAGACUGAUCUGAUGGACCAAAAUCGGAAUUUUGAAAAGCACCAGUACUACUUUCCAAAUGAUCAGCAGGUUAAACAUGUUCAGCAAGGUAUAGUAUGAAUCCAUUAACCCUUCGUUGUCCAGGGUCCAGACCAGAACUACUUGUUAGUUUUGAAAACAGUAGCCCAGGAUGUGGUUGUGUGCUUUAGGAAAGUCAGCAGUGCUGCAGGCUGUGUAGACAACCAAAGUUUACAAGGCUGGGAAGACACUUCUCCAAAUACAUAUACACCAGGCAUUUCUUUAAAAUCAAAAACAAUCCAUUAGCUUUGGGGCGGGGGGUGGGGGGAGGGUUAAAUGUAGGCCUUGGAAACAGUUUUAAGUGGCUUUUAAGUAUCUGCAUAGAGGCAAUCCUAAGGUUUGCUUUAAGUCUCUUAAAUCUAACAUUUUUAAAAGCAUUUCUUCCCUGUAUUUUCAUAUACAAGUUGGUUUUAAUUUUGUUUGGGUGGUGUUAUUUUUUUUAAAUGACUUUUUAGUUUAGAAAGUUCUGAUGAGCAAAUAAAUACAUCUAUCUACAUGUUGGAAGUCCAUCUGCCAGCACACCUGCUUAAAGUGAAAUGAAAGCACAUAACCAGGCUCUGAAUGGGUUAUAUUUUAUCAUGGUGCUCCCAGAAUCCUUUGACCUCACUCUGCUUUCUAGUCUGCUUGUGACACUGGACAGUCCUUUCUUACAGAGCUAUUAUAUGUUCUAGGCUACGAAGGGUUAAAUAAUCCCAAAAAUGAGGUAUGUCAUACCCACACGUCUUUAUCUCUAGAAGCUGUGAUGUAUGUGAAACAGCACUGUUAUUCUUAACACUAGUGUGUAAAAUAAGGAUUAGUACAGUACGUCUCAUUACUUUUUAAUUCAGGGCACCCUGAGUGAAAACAAAUACAAAAAAAAAUCCCUAACUCUGAGCUCUAUCUCUGAUUCCUCUUCCUCCUUCCCCUCUUCCUCCUCUUCCUCUCCUCCUGUUUUGCUACAUUCUCCUCAGUGGCAAAAAGUUUCACUCUACCUCUGACAGCAUGUAUAUUGCACCAGUAGCUAACAAAAACUGGUCUAGUCAAACCAAAUGGGCACAAAAGAACCAGGAUACCAAAAGUUAAGCUCAUACAGCUGCAAACCAUAUCACUUCUUGGUAACAAUGCAGACCUCAUAAACCUAAAGAAGAGAAAGAAAAGAAAACUUUUGUUACUUUCCUUUUUUGCUUGUCACUUAUAUACAGGCUAUGUGAGAAUAUAAUUUGUAGGUAUAACACAUUAAGAAAAAGUUAUCUUCAUUGGAUAGAAUUGAAUGGUGGUCGCUGAUAGGAAUAGGGCGUCCUCUAGCUCUUAUCUCUGUCUCUUACUCUUUUCUCUUUCUCUUUUUCUCUGUCAUGAGACUGUGUGUGACAGGGCCACCUGUCUUUUUUUUUUCUUAAAUUUUUUUUUUUUUUAUGUGUAGGUGCAUGUCUUGGGGAUUUAAAAAUUUCAAGGCUGGUUUACUUAUGCAAAGCAUGCCUACGUCUGGAAUACUUAGGGAAAGAAAGCGACUCCAUGUUGUCCGAAUUCCUCAAGGGACAGAAAAAAAAUUGGAGACUGUUGAAAUGCAGAUUUGAAGUAAUUUUUUUAAAAUAUUAUUUUGGGUUCUGCGACAUUGUGAAAAAUUAAAGUUGUUGUGCAAUACUUAAUUCAGACAUGUACCACAAGUUAAUGGUAGACUAACACUGGGGGGUGGGGUCUAGGCAUCAUGCUUUUGUCAGCAUACUCUUGAGCUUUUAAGUCUACUAUGUCUGAACUGUGGUUUCUUGUUUAUCCUUUUUUCCUUAGUUGGACUGUAAUGUAUGGUCUGUCAACCUGUGAAUCUUUAAAGUAUGAUUCAGGUAUUGUUGUAUUCUUUACUGUGUAAUAAAAAAGUUGAAAAAAAUCUGGAUCCUCUGUCUCCCUCGUCCCCGGUGUGCCAUGGUUGCCCACCAGUGACCCCAGCCUGAGGAGUCCAUCCUCCAUGGUGCUGAAUCAAAUCUGUAGAGUUUAUUCAGCUACAAAGCGUGGCUCUGUAACAGGAGUUGGCUUAUCCAUGCGUGUUGAGUAGGGAAUGAUGUCAGAACUUUGCAAAAGUCGAGCUCAUUCAUAAGGGGAUGUUUCUCAGGCAGGAGGAGUAGGAAGAGUGGGAGGAGAAUUACUACCUUCCAUAGGAAAGGAGAGCUUGGCUUGCCUAGAUUAGCUGCUGCAUAGAUAGCAGAGGCCCUUUUGGCUGUGUUUUGAUAAAAUUAGAAAUGAGUACCUAAAUCUGGAUCACUCUGCUCAGAGAGGUUCGUGCCAACCUCAUGAGGCUCUGACUCUUGUCAGGUUGCUUGGCUGCCUUGUGCAUACCCGAAUGGCAGAUCAGCUGACAUGACAUGGAACUGCUCUAUCUGCCUUGUCCCCUCUCCUCUAAUUAAAAGUCGCUACCAUUGUCACUCUUGGUUAUGUAGUUAAUAUCCACUGUGGCUAUCUCCAACUUGCUGGGACAUCCAGUUAUCUCCUCUGACACAUAUUUUUUCAUUCUCUAGUUACAAAGUUUGUUAGAGUUUGAAAAACAAACCCUUCUCCCCUACCCUGUGAAUGCUGUUAGUUUUUAUGUGUAGUUUUCAAAACACAGAUUAUCUUAUAUACUGUGUUGUAGCAGAAAUUCCUGUUUCCUCUGAAUGUUCUGACUUUAUAGACCAAAAUAAUCGUUGCAAAAAAUCAAGGAUGGCACAGCAGGUGCAUGAGCCCGUGUCUGGAGAAAGGUUAUGAAGGUGAAUGCUGGUUACAUGGGAGGGUGACUUGGAGCCCUCUAGUUUCCUUCUUGUGCCAGCUGGGUUCCUGUUUCAAGGCCAGGCUUCUCUAACUUGUCUUCCUGGGAAAUGUAGCUUUUCCAAGAAUUUGGUAGUGCACACCAGGAAAAACUAGGUAUCAGAACAGAUUUUUUUUUAAAUAGUGGAAACACCCUCACUCCCACACUUUGGACAGUUAGGGUUGGAUAUUUAAUUUCAUAGUUACUCUUUUUUUCCACAGAAGAAAGGCCAGCCUGACCCAAGUUGCCUAUUUUUAAUGUGUUACUGCAUCUUAUUUUCUCUUCAAAGUGAAAAAGGCCAGAAACUAGCAGAUAGAAAUGGAACCCGUUGACUUAGUUCCCUUAUAAGAAGUUCUUGCAAACACCUCUGUGACGUUUUCAUUCAAGUGGAUAUGUUGGACAAAUAGGAAACAGUUUUAGUUUACGCGAACAGUAUGAGACUUCCAGGUGGUGGACGCCAUUUUUUUAGAAGUGUUGAUGAUGUAUUUGAUAACAUUAUAAAAGUAUGUGUCUCCCGUGAAAGAACAUUGAGCUAUUUCCCUGGAAUGGAUGGGGAAGAAAUGAGCAAAGGAGUGCUGUUCUGUAUGGGUGUCUAUACCCUUAUUCCAAGGUGAAUAAAUAAAGUUGUGUUUGCCUAAUCAUG